CAGAAUGACUGUUGCCAGCAUCUAGAAGGAAUUACUUUUCCAGGCAGUGCAAUCAUGCUAUUUAUCAAAAGAAACAUUGGACAAUCAGAAUGGGCUGCAGAGCUGUGUCCUGAGCUGUCUGGCCAACUCCCGGCAAGAAGCUUCUUUGUCCUUUAAAGACUGAACUUUAUCCUCAAGCAGUAACAGGACUGGAAUGAAAGGAGUUUGGAAUUAUUCUGCUUUGAGCCGAAGAGAAGAUGAAACACGAACCCAGAGGAGCAGGAUGACAGACAGAGUCCCUUGUUCCAAAUGUUUCCAGGUUCACUGCCAGAUUUCUGUUCUGAAUUGUGUUUAUUACCCAGAACUCUUUGUCUGGGUCAGUCAAGAACCAUUUCCAAACAAGGACAUGGAGGGAAGGCUUCCUAAGGGAAGACUUCCUGUCCCAAAGGAAGUGAACCGCAAGAAGAACGAUGAGACAAACGCUGCCUCCCUGACUCCACUGGGCAGCAGUGAACUCCGCUCCCCAAGAAUCAGUUACCUCCACUUUUUUUAAUCGUAACACCUCCAUUUGUAUUACAUAUGGUGUAUGGGUAUUGAUGAGGUCAUGGUAUCAUAUAUGGGAUUUUUUUCUGUGUAAAUCAUCAAGUAUAAGAAGAAACUAUGGGACUCUGAGCCUUGCUUUAGAGAAUUUACAGUGGACAAAUAGGUGUCAUCAAACCAGUUUUUAAUCAUUCUGACUCAAGUGAAAACGCUCAGAAUUUCACACUGUGAAUCCACGUUUACAACCCUUACAGGUGGGCCUUCAGGCCUGGUUCGCUACAACAAUGUCUUCCACAACUCAAACUCCCACCGCGCUCACACAACCGGUCCACUCCUGCCUUUUCACUCACACAGCUCCCGACUGCUUCUUGCAGAGGCUGAGAGUCCCCCCCCCACCUUUUUUUUCAUUUAGAUGUAACAAACCUAGUAGUUUAUGUUCAUCAAUUGUCUGUAUAUCUCUAUAUUUUAUCCAUGUACUCUUUUGAUGUAUAGAAGUAGUUUGAAACUCAUUGUUUCCUUGUGGUAAGUGACCGAGAUGCUGCCACAGGACCUGAGACACUGAUGAAUGGUGCUAUUUUGGACUUUCAACAUGCUCCUUGGCGAGGUAGCUCUGAUGGAGUUAUUUUUUAUUUCCAUGUUCUAAGAAGGUGUUGGUACUCUGUUUCCCUGAAUGUUGUUCUCUAGACUGGAUUGACUUGUUUUCCUUGUGUCUUCAGUGUGGCUUUCUUCCUCAGUGUUGUAGGUUGAGCGAAUGCUACCAGAGUGUGAGAGACCAUUGUCUCGUUGGCUGGCGCUCACGGACAUGCAGUCACGGUAGCGGGAGCAAUCACAAAACUGUAAUUUACUUACCAAAUCUCUUCCUUUCCGUAGCCUCGCCUGCCUGACUUAGAGAAAGAAAAGCAAUAAUUUUACAGGCAUUUUGAGGUGUCUCUUUGGGUUCUUUCUGUUUGAAAGGAUAUUUGUCGAAAAAAAGAGCAAAACCGUUUUAAAUAAACUCCCCCUGGAAAAAAACCCAAAACACUGGCAUCUGAGUGGGAAUAUGAAAAUGACACCUUUUCCAAAUAUUAAAUUGGAAAACAAGGUCUACAAAAUCAUGAUACUUUUUUAAAAGGCAGAGCAUUCUUUUUUCGGCAAUUUUGAUAAGCAAGGUGUAGAUUUACAUUUUUGUCCUUGCUCCCAACGAAAUGGAUAAACAAAAAUAAAUUACCAUCUACUCAUGGAAUGUUGUUGUGUUAGCCAGUCUGAAAGCCCACCUUAAUUUUUAUAUAACUGUCUUUAGCUCUUCUUUUGACAGGGCAGGCCUUGUUCUGAACUGUUUCGCUUCUGACUGUUAAACACCGAUGACGCAUGCACUGCACUUCUUCGUUUUCUUCUUGCUCCCCCAUUGGCCUGAGUUUCUUGUGCAUUACUCCUCUCCCUCCUUCGUUAGAAUAGGUAUAUCAGCUGUGUAAAUAGAGCAAGAAAACAGUAUUCUGCAUCUGUGGCAUUUAUGUAGAGUUGCAGUUGUGUACUGCUGAAAAUGCAGGCUUUUGUAACAGUGUGAUCUUUACUGAUGCACUCAUGACAAGUACCCAAUGUAUUUUAGCUAUUUUAGUAGUAUUUGUUCAAUAAAUACGCAAGCUGUAAGGUAACUGUCUGAUUUGGCUCAUCAUUGAAGAGGCCUAGUUUUGAAUGUCUUCUCUGGUUCUUGCUAAUUCAUGUGUUUCCAGAGCCCCAGAAGUCAGGCCAGCAAACCCAAGGGCAAAUAUCAAAAGAGAGAGAAUCAGCUCUGCCUUUCAUGCGUUUUCCCUUUUGAGGAUUUUAUGAGAUUAGGGGCUAGGCAGUGGCUCAUUAAGAUGGUAUUUGCAGAGCUGCCUCUGGACACAAAGCAGAAUUAGACCAAGAUCCUUUUAUUUCUACACUUUUUCUCCCUUCCAAGGCAUUCCCAUACGCUUCAAAACUUACUCUUUCUCACUCCUUGCCAUUAAGACCCACUCUGUGGUAUUCUUUAAGACCCACUCUGUGGUAUUCUUUCUUUUUCCCUGCCAAAAGAGAUCUGACCUCCCUUCUUCAUGGAAUAUGUGCACUUUUCCUCAGACAAAAAGCUUAAACUUUUGUAAGAGGAUAAAAAUUUGAGACAGAAUUUAAAGUCA